AGAGGCGGGCGCCACACUUGAAGAGGCUGAGGGAGGCGGUGUCGCCGCCGCGGCGCUGUCAUGGAGCUAGCGCAGGAAGCGCGGGAACUGGGUUGCUGGGCGGUCGAAGAGAUGGGGGUGCCCGUGGCGGCCCGGGCCCCGGAAUCGACGCUGCGCAGGCUGUGUCUGGGCCAGGGGGCUGACAUCUGGGCCUACAUCUUGCAGCAUGUGCACAGUCAGAGGACUGUCAAGAAGAUCCGGGGAAACCUACUCUGGUAUGGCCACCAGGACAGUCCACAGGUCCGUCGGAAGUUAGAGCUGGAAGCUGCUGUGACCCGCCUGCGGGCAGAAAUCCAGGAACUCGACCAGAGCCUGGAGCUGAUGGAGCGAGACACUGAGGCUCAGGACACGGCCAUGGAGCAGGCACGUCAGCACACUCAAGACACCCAGCGUCGAGCUCUCCUCCUCCGGGCCCAAGCUGGGGCCAUGCGAAGACAGCAGCAUACGCUCCGAGAUCCCAUGCAGCGGCUGCAGAAUCAACUGAGGCGCCUGCAGGACAUGGAGAGGAAAGCCAAAGUAGAUGUGACCUUUGGAUCCCUCACGUCGGCAGCUCUGGGCCUGGAGCCCGUGGUCCUGCGUGAUGUCCGAACAGCCUGCACCCUCCGGGCCCAGUUCCUGCAGAACCUCCUGCUUCCCCAGGCCAAGAGGGGCAGCCUCCCAACCCCUCAUGAUGACCACUUUGGCACUUCGUACCAGCAGUGGCUGAGCUCAGUGGAGACGCUGCUGACAAACCACCCCCCAGGCCACGUCCUGGCUGCCUUGGAGCACCUGGCUGCAGAGCGGGAGGCAGAGAUUCGGUCCCUGUGCAGUGGGGAUGGGCUUGGCGACACAGAGAUAUCCAGACCCCAGGCCCCGGACCAGUCAGACUCCAGCCAGACCCUGCCGUCCAUGGUUCAUCUCAUCCAGGAGGGCUGGCGGACUGUGGGUGUGCUGGUCUCCCAGCGGAGCACCCUCCUGAAGGAGCGGCAAGUCUUGACCCAGCGCCUCCAGGGCCUGGUGGAGGAGGUGGAGAGACGCGUCCUGGGAUCCAGUGAGAGGCAGGUGCUGAUACUGGGGCUUCGGCGCUGUUGCCUGUGGACGGAGCUCAAGGCCCUGCACGAUCAGAGCCAGGAGCUGCAGGAUGCAGCUGGGCAUCGGCAGCUCCUGCUGAGGGAGCUACAGGCCAAACAGCAGCGGAUCCUGCACUGGCGCCAGCUGGUGGAGGAGACCCAGGAACAGGUCCGCCUGCUCAUCAAGGGAAACUCGGCCAGCAAGACCCGCCUGUGCCGGAGCCCGGGGGAGGUGCUAGCUCUGGUCCAGCGAAAGGUGGUCCCUACAUUUGAGGCAGUGGCACCACAGAGCCGGGAGCUGCUGCGCUGUCUGGAGGAGGAAGUCCGGCAUUUGCCCCACAUUCUGUUGGGCACGCUGCUGCGGCACAGGCCGGGAGAGUUGAAGCCCCUGCCCACGGUCCUCCCAUCCAUCCACCAGCUGCACCCCGCGUCCCCAAGGGGCUCCAGCUUCAUAGCGCUGAGCCACAAGCUGGGGCUGCCUCCAGGGAAGGCCUCGGAGCUGCUCCUGCCGGCGGCUGCCUCUCUUCGCCAGGACCUUCUGCUCCUGCAGGACCAGCGGAGCCUCUGGUGCUGGGAUCUACUCCACAUGAAGACCAGCCUGCCGCCAGGCCUUCCCACCCAGGAGCUGCUGCAGAUCCAGGCAUCCCAGGAAAAACAGCAGAAAGAGAACCUGGGGCAGGCUCUGAAGAGGCUGGAGAAGCUACUGAAACAGGCACUGGAGCGAAUCCCUGAGCUGCAGGGGAUCGUGGGGGACUGGUGGGAGCAGCCAGGCCAGGCCGCCCUCUCUGAGGAGCUCUGCCAGGGCCUGUCCCUGCCCCAGUGGCGGCUGCGCUGGGUUCAGGCCCAGGGGGCCCUGCAGAAGCUGUGCAGCUGAAGAGAGGGUUCAAACGGAAGCCGAGAACUUGACACUGUUCACCCCAACACCUCACCUCCCCCAGGACAUUUGGAAGAAAGCAGCGCCAGGAUUCCUCGGCAGUCGUCCCCACCCGCACCUGCAGUCCCCUCAUGUGCUGUUCUGCUGCCCCACUCAGCUCCUGGACCCUGUCCUUUCAUCCCGCUAAAGCACCCCCUAAAACCCCUUCAUCACUUUCAUUCUCAGCAAAAAGUAAUUGAGCACCUCCUCUAGGCGCUGGGGAGUCCACACUGAACAAAAGAAACAGAAAACCCUGUCUUCCAGCAGUUGAGUUCUAGGGCAGGGAGACAGAGUUUACAAGAUAAGGAAAAUAUAUAUGUAGUAUGCUGCAAGUUAACUGCUGUGUGGGAAAUCCAGCAGGGGGUGGGAUGUGUGAUUUGAAUUGAGGGCCACACUGCCCAGGUCGUGCUCCGUCAAGGGGUGAGCAGGAGCAACAGGGGUGGCUGAGUAAGGGCUUGCAGCUGGAGGCAACAGCACAUGCAAAGGCCCUGAGCCAGGAUGUGCUGCAAUAAGGGCCACUGAGGGGGACAGUGUAGGUUGGGGGUGAGGAAUGUAUUAAAAGAUGAGAUUGCCUUCUAGUUUGUAUAGUUUCUUUUUUUACAUGUAAAUCAGCCAUUUGGAAUUUAUCCUAGCACAUGGAUCCAAUUUUGUCUUAUUUUACAUAUAUCCUAGUAGCACUUACUGAAAUUCCCAGUCAGAGUGGCAGUUGCCUCUGAGGGAAGGUGGGUGGCAGGGAUCAACUGAGGAGGAGACACAGAAAUGUCCUAGCUGAUGGGAAUGUGCUGUGUCAAGAGCAGCGGCGGUGACGCAGGUGUAGAGAUUUGUCAGAGCUCAUGUAGUUGUAGUCUUAAGGCCUGUGCAUUUCACUGCGUGGGUUACUCAAUUUAUAAAGCAAAGCCCUUACACUUUUGAGAUGCCACCUUUUUAUGCACUAAAUUUCCAUGUUUAAUUGGGUUAUAUCUGGCUUCUCUCCAGACCUGCUUUGUAUUUAACUCUCCAUGUGUCAUUCCUACAGUAGCUUAAUAGAAAGGCUUGUGACACAUUGUCAUAUCUGUUCUUGUUUUCUUUUGUUUUUUUUUUUUUUUUUUUUGAGAUGCAGUCUCAUUCUGUUGCCCAAGUUGGAGUGCAGUGGCAUGAUCUCAGCUCACUGCAACCUCCGCCUCCCAGGUUCAAGCCAUUCUCAUGCCUCAGCUUCCCCAGUAGCUAGGAUUACAGGUACGCACCACCACGCCCAGCUCAUUUUUGUACUUUUAGUAGGGACGGGGUUUCAUCAUGUUGGCCAGACUGGUCUCGAACUCCUGACCUCAAGUGAUCUGCCUGCCUCGGCCUCCCAAAGUGCUGGGAUUACAGGCAUGAGCCACCGCGCCUGACCACAUUGCCAUAUCUGAAAUGGCUGGAUUCUCUUAGGUGCUUUUCUUUUUCUUUCUUUCUUUCUUUUUUUGAGACAGAAUCUGGCUGUUUCCCAGGCUGAAGUGCAGUGGCAUGAACUCAGCUCACUGCAACCUCUGCCUCCUGGAUUCAAACAAUUCUCAUGUCUCAGCCUCCUGAAUAGCUGGGAUUACAGGCACCCACCACCAUAUCUGGCUAAUAUUUGUAUUUUUUGUAGAGUCGGAGCUUUACCAUGUUGGUCAGGCUGCUCUCCAACUCCUGGCCUCAAGUGAUUCUAUCGCCUCUGCCUCCCAAAUCUUCACCUGCUGGGAUUAGUUUCCCCUGUCUCAGUAAAUUUUUUUUCCCAAACUAAGUGAACAUUAGAUUUAAUUUGGCUGGCCCCAGAAGAAAAACAUGCACAGAUGGUAGUUUUACUGGUGUUGCAGUAAGUUUUCAAAUUUGGAAGUUUGGCAGCUUUAUGAUCUUGAACCUUGCUGUCCAUCUCUCACACAACUCCUCUCUUGGCCUCCAGAGUCCCUUUACUCUCCCAGCUUUCCUCCUGCCCCUGGCUGCUGUUUCCCAGCCUUUCCACAUUGGCUUUCCCAUGUAGUCCUUAGUGUGUCUGCUCCUCCUCUCUCUCCUCAUCACAGUUCCCAGCCCCCACCUUCAACUGAACUCAACAAAAUCUUCAACUUCAUACAGUAGUCACAUUGUUAGUAAUAACACUGGCAUUUUUAUUUUGAUAAAAUAGACCGUUUAAAUUUUUGAGAUUCUACCUUAUAUUUUUUGAAUUAUAUACUAAAGCAAAUAAGUAGUGAUGUAAUGUCAUUGGGGACCAAGAUUUUUAGUGUAAAUGAAAAAAGAUAACAAAUAUAAACUCAAGUAAACACCCUGUAGUCUUUCACAUGAAUUGGAAAUAUCAGAAUAAAGUCAUGAUUUUUCUCUUUCUAAAAAA